GAUCUCCUCCCACUGCACCAGCCAGCAGGUUCAUGUUCGAGGCCAUCUUCCCCUCCACACCCCAAGCCAGGCUGAAGAGAGAUCCACGGGAAAAGCCGGGCCUGUCCUCAUUCAGGUCCACAUUCAGGCAACAAAGCUCACUUGGUCUUUGCAUCCCACGCCUCAUGUUACCUAAGGAGGCCAGCCCAUCUCAGAGGCACAGUUCGAUGUCCAGCUCGAUGGCCAGGGCCCUGGUGCUCCUCCAGAGCAUGGCCAGCCGGGACGCCCGGUGCCCAGAAUGGAAACCGCACCAAAAGCCACGCACGCUCAGCAAGUCGGUCCAGACCAUCAGCCGCUACUACAGGAAGACGAGUGAACCCAAGGAUGCCGCCAGCCUCACCGGCUUCAUGUCCAAAAUGGAACUUCGAAGGGUCUUCCCCACGCAUCCUGACUGCCCCCAGUUCAGCACCAGGGCCACAUCCAUGUCCCACUGUGGUUCACCCACUGAGGCCGAUUUGUCCGGAGAGAUUGACAACAGCUCGGAGACCUGGAGAGGCACCCAGGACCUGUUCUUGGCCAGGCGGGGCUCAGACACGAACGUGGACGGGUACCUCCUUCCCUUCAGUAAGAGCAUCUGCGAGUUCGAUUACUUGCGGAAGAGGAGAAAAUCCCAGACUUUGAGUCCGGUCACCAGCAGCUCAGUCGCAUCUCAGAGCUGCCUGAGAAAGAGGAUGCCCUGGUACCUCUCAGUCAUCCACGAGAAGGAUCACUGCCUGUCUGAGCUGGAGAUACAGGUUCAGAAGAAAGACGAGGAGAUCCUGCUGCUCCAGGAGGAGAGGGAGGCCCUGAAGAUGCAGCUGAAAUGCCUUCUGAAAGGCAAAGGCCAAGAGACAUCCAUGUCCCCAGGCAGGAGGGAGCAGCUCUCAGACGCUUCGCUGAAGCUGGGCAGGCUGAGCCUCCUGAAGGCCUUCUCCAGACAUGAGGAGGAGCUGCAGCACUGGUGGCAGAUGCAGGAGGAGUCUGCGGCACCGGAGAGGGGCAAGGAGCCCGACCUGGGAGGUGGCGAGGAGGACGAGGGCCUGGAAGGGGAGCCCGAUGGGGUGGAGGACACGGGUGCCUGGGGAGGUGUGAGCCAGAUGGGAUCCGUGCAUGAGGAGGGAAGCGAGGAGGAGGAAGAGGAGGAAGGGGACAGGGAUGAGGACUCAGAGGAAAGGGAGCUGCCGGAGGAAGAGGAGAUCCCCAGGAGAAGGGCCUCCUCCCUGGCCGAGUCGUUUGAGGAGGAGCUGCUGGCCCAGCUGGAGGAGUACGAGCAGGUCAUCCUGGACUUCCAGUUCAACCUGGAGGCCACCAGGACCAGAUACUCCCUUGCAACAGGAGUGAUUGCGUCUUUACAACAACAAGUGGAUUUCCAAGAAACCCAGCUGCGAAAGAUCAAUACGGAAAAUGAGACGCUGCAGAAGGAGCUCCGAGAGCGGAGGCAGCAGCUACAAGCCAUGACCGACAAGUUCUCCAACCUCCGAGAAGAUAAGAAACACCAAGAGAUGAUGGGGCUCAUUGAAAAGGACAACCAGCUCCUCCGACAGCAAGUGUCGGAACUGGAGAGAAAGCUCACCAAGCGGGACUGUGUCAUCUCAGAGUUGGACACCAAGGUCAGCCAGCUGCAGGAGCAGGUGGAACUGGACCAGAACCACCUGCAGAGGUGGAAGCAGCUGCAGGAGGAUUUGCAGAGCAAGAAGGAGAUGAUUCAGCAGGCAGAGCAGCACACCCGCGUGGCCCUGGAGAGCUCCCAGUCCAGGCUCGAGAGGUUAAGGAAUAAGAUCAUCCAGGCCACCUUUAGCAUCUCCGGGACCAAGUCCUUGGCCAACGAGAUCUCUGACAAUGACAUCCUGGAAGCCCUGCAGAGAAUUAUCUCAGAGAGAAGCGACUACUAUAAUCAGCUGAAGCAGAAAGGCGUCAAAGUGCCCCCCCUGCAACAGUCAGAGGCCUUCCUGACCAGCAAAUCCAAGAAGGGGACCUCCAAGUAGGCCCAGCCAGGCCCCCAAAUACGGUCAGCCCAGCAGAGGCCGGGGCCCAGCUCCAGAACCACCCGCCCCCACCAUGCGUCCUGCUCUCAGACUCAGAAUUAAACCCCGGUGUUGGCACUGUC